ACCGCCAUCAUGAUCUGCCUGGUGCUGACCAUCUUCGCUAACCUCUUCCCCGCGGCCUGCACCGGCGCACACGAACGCACCUUCCUGGCCGUGAAGCCGGACGGCGUGCAGCGGCGGCUGGUGGGCGAGAUUGUGCGGCGCUUCGAGAGGAAGGGCUUCAAGUUGGUGGCGCUGAAGCUGGUGCAGGUGGGGGCGCGGCCUCCGAGGAGCUGCUGCGUGAGCACUACGCCGAGCUGCGUGAACGCCCGUUCUACGGCCGCCUUGUCAAGUAUAUGGCCUCCGGGCCGGUGGUGGCCAUGGUAUGGCAGGGGCUGGACGUGGUGCGCACCUCGCGGGCGCUCAUCGGAGCCACGAACCCGGCCGACGCCCCGCCCGGCACCAUCCGCGGGGAUUUCUGCAUCGAGGUUGGCAAGAACCUGAUUCACGGCAGCGACUCGGUGGAGAGUGCCCGCCGCGAGAUCGCUCUCUGGUUCCGCGCAGACGAGCUCCUCUGCUGGGAGGACAGCGCUGGGCACUGGCUGUAUGAGUAGCCCGGCAGAUGCGCGUCACAGAGGCUCUCACACUCCAGCCUCCUCCAGGGCCCAGGUGGGCGGGCUUCUGGCCCCACCCCACAGCGCUUGGAGCAUCCCUUUGGACGGGCUGCUGAACAUCCACCUGUCUGGACGUUGCAUGGAGGGUGGCGCAGGCCUCUCCAAUCCCUGGCGUACAGGGUUUCCUGCCCGAGGAGCUGCUCCAGGAGCCUGCGCGGCUCGCCUGGAAACGUGCCAGGACACUGUCCUGGUGCCCAGCCCAACGUGGUCCAACGUUUUUUUAUAAUAAAGUCCUCGUUUUCGUUUCGAUUUGGGCCCAGGAACAGGCA